AGAGAAGAAGCCAGGAAUCAGAGGACAGGGAGGCAGGAUGCGGCUCAGUCUGUGAAUGCUCGUUUGAAAACUUGGAACUGUUCUAUGAUGGAGCAAGCAGUCAUCUGUGGCCCCUAACGCAUCCUGGCCACUGCACAAAGCAUUUCCGAGCAGAAAUUUCCAAGCGACCAUGCCCUGUGAGGUAUGGCCACCGCAACACCGAGGCACUCUUUAUUAAACACCGAAACUUGGGUUCUGGCACCCCUUUCAGACAUGAAUCAGCUUCGUUCCUCCUCCAGGGCCUCCCUCUGGUGGCUCUGGUUCCCACUGCUCCACUCCACACCCUCUAACAGGGUGCUACAGGACCUGGGAGGAAGAGCCCUUCUUUGCGGAAUGCUAGACUGGACAGGGAAGAACGCCUCAAGUGAGCACGCCUACAACUCCAGUAAACACCCUGCGCACGCUCCCCCACAACCCCCGUGUGCUAGCACGCCAAUGCACAUGCGGACAGCCCACCCCAAGGGAAGAAUCAGAGAAGAAGGAACGCAAGACCCCGGAAGUAUGGCAGCAUAUAAAACCCCAGGUCAAAAGGCCAAAUCUCACACUUCAUCUCUCAAGUUGCCCGCCUAACCACCUUCAAAGUGUACUUGACGUCCUUUCAUUCCUGCUCUGAAGUUUUUAAUAAACUUUCACUGCUGCUCUAAAA